AUGACCCCAAUACGCAAAACUAACCCCCUAAUAAAAUUAAUUAACCACUCAUUCAUCGACCUCCCCACCCCAUCCAACAUCUCCGCAUGAUGAAACUUCGGCUCACUCCUUGGCGCCUGCCUGAUCCUCCAAAUCACCACAGGACUAUUCCUAGCCAUGCACUACUCACCAGACGCCUCAACCGCCUUUUCAUCAAUCGCCCACAUCACUCGAGACGUAAAUUAUGGCUGAAUCAUCCGCUACCUUCACGCCAAUGGCGCCUCAAUAUUCUUUAUCUGCCUCUUCCUACACAUCGGGCGAGGCCUAUAUUACGGAUCAUUUCUCUACUCAGAAACCUGAAACAUCGGCAUUAUCCUCCUGCUUGCAACUAUAGCAACAGCCUUCAUAGGCUAUGUCCUCCCGUGAGGCCAAAUAUCAUUCUGAGGGGCCACAGUAAUUACAAACUUACUAUCCGCCAUCCCAUACAUUGGGACAGACCUAGUUCAAUGAAUCUGAGGAGGCUACUCAGUAGACAGUCCCACCCUCACACGAUUCUUUACCUUUCACUUCAUCUUGCCCUUCAUUAUUGCAGCCCUAGCAACACUCCACCUCCUAUUCUUGCACGAAACGGGAUCAAACAACCCCCUAGGAAUCACCUCCCAUUCCGAUAAAAUCACCUUCCACCCUUACUACACAAUCAAAGACGCCCUCGGCUUACUUCUCUUCCUUCUCUCCUUAAUGACAUUAACACUAUUCUCACCAGACCUCCUAGGCGACCCAGACAAUUAUACCCUAGCCAACCCCUUAAACACCCCUCCCCACAUCAAGCCCGAAUGAUAUUUCCUAUUCGCCUACACAAUUCUCCGAUCCGUCCCUAACAAACUAGGAGGCGUCCUUGCCCUAUUACUAUCCAUCCUCAUCCUAGCAAUAAUCCCCAUCCUCCAUAUAUCCAAACAACAAAGCAUAAUAUUUCGCCCACUAAGCCAAUCACUUUAUUGACUCCUAGCCGCAGACCUCCUCAUUCUAACCUGAAUCGGAGGACAACCAGUAAGCUACCCUUUUACCAUCAUUGGACAAGUAGCAUCCGUACUAUACUUCACAACAAUCCUAAUCCUAAUACCAACUAUCUCCCUAAUUGAAAACAAAAUACUCAAAUGGGCCU